GCCGUCGUUGUUGGCCACAGCGUGGGAAGCAGCUCUGGGGGAGCUCGGAGCUCCCGAUCACGGCUUCUUGGGGGUAGCUACGGCUGGGUGUGUAGAACGGGGCCGGGGCUGGGGCUGGGUCCCCUAGUGGAGACCCAAGUGCGAGAGGCAAGAACUCUGCAGCUUCCUGCCUUCUGGGUCAGUUCCUUAUUCAAGUCUGCAGCCGGCUCCCAGGGAGAUCUCGGUGGAACUUCAGAAACGCUGGGCAGUCUGCCUUUCAACCAUGCCCCUGUCCCUGGGAGCCGAGAUGUGGGGGCCUGAGGCCUGGCUGCUGCUGCUGCUACUGCUGGCAUCAUUUACAGGCCGGUGCCCCGCGGGUGAGCUGGAGACCUCAGACGUGGUAACUGUGGUGCUGGGCCAGGACGCAAAACUGCCCUGCUUCUACCGAGGGGACUCCGGCGAGCAAGUGGGGCAAGUGGCAUGGGCUCGGGUGGACGCGGGCGAAGGCGCCCAGGAACUAGCGCUACUGCACUCCAAAUACGGGCUUCAUGUGAGCCCGGCUUACGAGGGCCGCGUGGAGCAGCCGCCGCCCCCACGCAACCCCCUGGACGGCUCAGUGCUCCUGCGCAACGCAGUGCAGGCGGAUGAGGGCGAGUACGAGUGCCGGGUCAGCACCUUCCCCGCCGGCAGCUUCCAGGCGCGGCUGCGGCUCCGAGUGCUGGUGCCUCCCCUGCCCUCACUGAAUCCUGGUCCAGCACUAGAAGAGGGCCAGGGCCUGACCCUGGCAGCCUCCUGCACAGCUGAGGGCAGCCCAGCCCCCAGCGUGACCUGGGACACGGAGGUCAAAGGCACAACGUCCAGCCGUUCCUUCAAGCACUCCCGCUCUGCUGCCGUCACCUCAGAGUUCCACUUGGUGCCUAGCCGCAGCAUGAAUGGGCAGCCACUGACUUGUGUGGUGUCCCAUCCUGGCCUGCUCCAGGACCAAAGGAUCACCCACAUCCUCCACGUGUCCUUCCUUGCUGAGGCCUCUGUGAGGGGCCUUGAAGACCAAAAUCUGUGGCACAUUGGCAGAGAAGGAGCUAUGCUCAAGUGCCUGAGUGAAGGGCAGCCCCCUCCCUCAUACAACUGGACACGGCUGGAUGGGCCUCUGCCCAGUGGGGUACGAGUGGAUGGGGACACUUUGGGCUUUCCCCCACUGACCACUGAGCACAGCGGCAUCUACGUCUGCCAUGUCAGCAAUGAGUUCUCCUCAAGGGAUUCUCAGGUCACUGUGGAUGUUCUUGACCCCCAGGAAGACUCUGGGAAGCAGGUGGACCUAGUGUCAGCCUCGGUGGUGGUGGUGGGUGUGAUCGCCGCACUCUUGUUCUGCCUUCUGGUGGUGGUGGUGGUGCUCAUGUCCCGAUACCAUCGGCGCAAGGCCCAGCAGAUGACCCAGAAAUAUGAGGAGGAGCUGACCCUGACCAGGGAGAACUCCAUCCGGAGGCUGCAUUCCCAUCACACGGACCCCAGGAGCCAGCCGGAGGAGAGUGUAGGGCUGAGAGCCGAGGGCCACCCUGAUAGUCUCAAGGACAACAGUAGCUGCUCUGUGAUGGUGAGGCCCCCGGCCCCACCGGUGUCCCCACCACUCUCCUCGGGCCCCUGUCCUGGUCCCAGAUAUGAGUGAAGAGCCCGAGGGCCGCAGUUACUCCACGCUGACCACGGUGAGGGAGAUAGAAACACAGACUGAACUGCUGUCUCCAGGCUCUGGGCGGGCCGAGGAGGAGGAAGAUCAGGAUGAAGGCAUCAAACAGGCCAUGAACCAUUUUGUUCAGGAGAAUGGGACCCUACGGGCCAAGCCCACGGGCAAUGGCAUCUACAUCAAUGGGCGGGGACACCUGGUCUGACCCAGGCCUGCCUCCCUUCCCUAGGCCUGGCUCCUUCUGUUGACAUGGGAGAUUUUAGCUCAUCUUGGGGGCCUCCUUAAACACCCCCAUUUCUUGCGGAAGAUGCUCCCCAUCCCACUGACUGCUUGACCUUUACCUCCAACCCUUCUGUUCAUCGGGAGGGCUCCACCAAUUGAGUCUCUCCCACCAUGCAUGCAGGUCACUGUGUGUGUGCAUGUGUGCCUGUGUGAGUGUUGACUGACUGUGUGUGUGUGGAGGGGUGACUGUCCGUGGAGGGGUGACUGUGUCCGUGGUGUGUAUUAUGCUGUCAUAUCAGAGUCAAGUGAACUGUGGUGUAUGUGCCACGGGAUUUGAGUGGUUGCGUGGGCAACACUGUCAGGGUUUGGCGUGUGUGUCAUGUGGCUGUGUGUGACCUCUGCCUGAAAAAGCAGGUAUUUUCUCAGACCCCAGAGCAGUAUUAAUGAUGCAGAGGUUGGAGGAGAGAGGUGGAGACUGUGGCUCAGACCCAGGUGUGCGGGCAUAGCUGGAGCUGGAAUCUGCCUCCGGUGUGAGGGAACCUGUCUCCUACCACUUCGGAGCCAUGGGGGCAAGUGUGAAGCAGCCAGUCCCUGGGUCAGCCAGAGGCUUGAACUGUUACAGAAGCCCUCUGCCCUCUGGUGGCCUCUGGGCCUGCUGCAUGUACAUAUUUUCUGUAAAUAUACAUGCGCCGGGAGCUUCUUGCAGGAAUACUGCUCCGAAUCACUUUUAAUUUUUUUCUUUUUUUUUUCUUGCCCUUUCCAUUAGUUGUAUUUUUUAUUUAUUUUUAUUUUUAUUUUUUUUUAGAGAUGGAGUCUCACUAUGUUGCUCAGGCUGGCCUUGAACUCCUGGGCUCAAGCAAUCCUCCUGCCUCAGCCUCCCUAGUAGCUGGGACUUUAAGUGUACACCACUGUGCCUGCUUUGAAUCCUUUACGAAGAGAAAAAAAAAAUUAAAGAAAGCCUUUAGAUUUAUCCAAUGUUUACUACUGGGAUUGCUUAAAGUGAGGCCCCUCCAACACCAGGGGGUUAAUUCCUGUGAUUGUGAAAGGGGCUACUUCCAAGGCAUCUUCAUGCAGGCAGCCCCUUGGGAGGGCACCUGAGAGCUGGUAGAGUCUGAAAUUAGGGAUGUGAGCCUCGUGGUUACUGAGUAAGGUAAAAUUGCAUCCACCAUUGUUUGUGAUACCUUAGGGAAUUGCUUGGACCUGGUGACAAGGGCUCCUGUUCAAUAGUGGUGUUGGGGAGAGAGAGAGCAGUGAUUAUAGACCGAGAGAGUAGGAGUUGAGGUGAGGUGAAGGAGGUGCUGGGGGUGAGAAUGUCGCCUUUCCCCCUGGGUUUUGGAUCACUAAUUCAAGGCUCUUCUGGAUGUUUCUCUGGGUUGGGGCUGGAGUUCAAUGAGGUUUAUUUUUAGCUGGCCCACCCAGAUACACUCAGCCAGAAUACCUAGAUUUAGUACCCAAACUCUUCUUAGUCUGAAAUCUGCUGGAUUUCUGGCCUAAGGGAGAGGCUCCCAUCCUUCGUUCCCCAGCCAGCCUAGGACUUCGAAUGUGGAGCCUGAAGAUCUAAGAUCCUAACAUGUACAUUUUAUGUAAAUAUGUGCAUAUUUGUACAUAAAAUGAUAUUCUGUUUUUAAAUAAACAGACAAAACUUG